AGGCGGCGAAGAUGGCGGAGAACAGCGGUCGCGCCGGCAAGAGCAGCGGGAGCGGCGCGGGGAAGGGGGCGGUGUCCGCAGAGCAGUAAGAGUAAAUGUCAUGUAAGAAGACCCUAGGACAUUUUGGAGAGAAAGGUGAUUGCUGGCUUCAACCGCCUUCGGCAGGAACAGCGAGGCCUGGCAUCCAAAGCAGCUGAGUUGGAGAUGGAGUUGAAUGAGCACAGCCUAGUGAUCGAUACACUGAAGGAGGUAGAUGAAACUCGUAAGUGCUACCGCAUGGUUGGAGGAGUGCUGGUGGAGCGAACUGUCAAAGAGGUGCUGCCCGCUUUGGAGAACAACAAGGAGCAGAUACAGAAGAUCAUUGAGACACUGACACAGCAGCUUCAGGCAAAGGGAAAAGAACUAAAUGAAUUCCGGGAAAAGCACAACAUUCGUCUCAUGGGAGAAGAUGAGAAGCCAGCAGCCAAGGAAAACUCAGAAGGGGCUGGGGCUAAGGCCAGCUCAGCUGGAGUGUUGGUCUCCUAGGGACCAAGGCCUUUGCAUUUUUUUCUACCCUGACUCCCACUUCUAAUUUCUCUUUAUUGUUAUUAUUAUUAUUUUCUCUGCUAUUGUAAUAUUUUUUUGUUAAUUAAAUGUUUUGGUCAGAA